AAUCGCCCCACAUGUCAGCGGUUGGUCGCCUCGCGGUGCAGUGCUGGGCACGCGAGCCCCUCCCGCAGUCAUUCUCAGCACAAGCACCAGCCUGGAGCCCCGCAGCGACAGAGCUGAGAGCCCCCAAGCCGCAGAGGUCGUGCGGAGCAGGUUGCAAAUGUCUUAGAAACACACUCCUGGACCACAGCUUCAAGAGACGCAAGCAGUCACCUCAUCUGCUGGUUUCCAAGCUGCCCUGCCAGAAGCAGGUCAGGGGUCCCACAGGGGUCCUCAGUAACUCCUCAAAAUCCUCUCCCAUCAAUGGCCCCACCAGAUCAUCCCUACUUUUGAAUGCUUGUCCAAUGCAGGUUCCAGGUUUCCUCUCUGACCACUUUUUGGACUGAAGAAUGGGCUCCAAGGGAUGGCUCCUGCCAUCUAGUGGCUUCCUGAUGUAUGGCAGAUUGUUCCUGGCUUUCAAAUUUCCACACCUUGAAAGAUGCCCAGGGAGCCUAUGAAAAGCCCAAGACCUGGCUGGGCGCGGCGGCUCAGGCCUGUAAUCCCAGCACUUUGGAAGACCGAGACGGGUGGAUCACCUGAAGUCAGGAGUUCAAGACGAGCCUGGCCAACAUGGCAAAACCCCGUCUCUACUAAAAAAUACAAAAAAAAAAAAAAAAAAUUGGGCGUGGUGGCAGGUGCCUGUAAUCCCAGCUACUCGGGAGUCUGAGGCAGGAGAAUCGCUUGAAGCUGGGAGGCAGAGGUUGCAGUGAGCUGAGAUUGCACCAUCGCAUUCCAGCCUGGCGACAGAGCAAGACUCCAUCUCAAAAAAAAAAAAAAAAAAAAAAAAAAAAAGAGAGAGAGAAAAGAAAAGCCCAAGACCUCGGGGCCAUCCCCAAACCUACUGUUAUCAGAUUUUGAAUCUAUCUUUUUUUCUCUUAAGAGACAGGCUCUCACUCUGUUGCCCAGGCUGGAGU